AAGUGACAUCACAAAUACUAGAGAUAAUGGCUCAAAGCUGCCUGCAUUGAGCCCACAUCUAAACAAACAGCAAUUUGCCCAUAUGUGACUAAGGCAGAGAAAGACAGCACCCAAUCAAUGUGAGACGAGACCCCAGCAUCCCUAUCUAUGGACUCCGACAGUCCAUCUUAUUAAAUACCAGGCUUCAGGACUGCUAUGUGGACUCACCGGCUCUCACCAACAUCUGGAUGGCCAGAACAUGUGCAAAGCAGAACAUUAAUGCCCCAGCACCAGCUACCACUUCCUCUUGGGAAGUUGUAAGGAACCCAUUAAUUGCCAGUUCCUUCUCCCUGGUUAAGCUUGUACUCAGGCGGCAACUGAAGAAUAAGUGCUGCCCACCACCAUGCAAGUUUGGAGAAGGAAAACUCUCGAAGAGAUUAAAGCACAAGGACGAUUCAGUGAUGAAAGCCACCCAGCAGGCCAGGAAAAGAAACUUCAUCAGUUCCAAGAGCAAGCAGCCAGCAGGGCAUAGGAGGCCUGCAGGAGGCAUCAGAGAGAGUAAAGAAAGUUCAAAGGAGAAAAAACUAACAGUCCGCCAAGAUCUUGAGGACAGAUAUGCUGAACAUGUGGCUGCCACCCAAGCGCUACCCCAGGACAGUGGGACAGCAGCCUGGAAGGGCCGAGUGUUGCUUCCUGAAACCCAAAAGAGACAGCAGUUGUCGGAGGACACGCUAACCAUCCAUGGUCUCCCCACAGAGGGUUACCAGGCUCUGUACCACGCUGUGGUGGAGCCAAUGCUGUGGAAUCCUUCAGGGACCCCCAAGAGGUACAGCCUGGAGCUGGGCAAGGCCAUUAAACAAAAGCUCUGGGAGGCUCUUUGCAGUCAGGGUGCCAUCUCUGAAGGUGCUCAGAGGGACCGGUUCCCUGGCAGGAAGCAGCCAGGUGUCCACGAGGAGCCUGUACUCAAGAAAUGGCCCAAGUUAAAGAGCAAAAAAUAGGAACAAGAACUCAUGGGAUUAGAGUAUUCUCUGCUAGAGAUCUGAAAAAUAAACACAACUUUGCACCUUC